AGCCAGACCCCGCGCCGCCCGCGCCCCGCUCGACUCCGGAGGCUCCCGCAGCCCCGGCGUCCGCCCCGCUGCCCCCUCCCCCGGGGGCCAUGGGGGCGCCCCCGGGCUACCGGCCCUCAGCUUGGGUGCAUCUCCUCCACCAGCUGCCCCGCGCCGACUUCCAGCUCCGCCCGGUGCCCAGCGUUUUCGCGCCCCAAGAGCAGGAAUACCAGCAGGCCUUGUUGCUGGUGGCGGCCUUGGCGGGCCUGGGCUUGGGCCUGAGCCUCAUUUUCAUCGCUGUCUACCUCAUCCGCUUCUGCUGCUGCCGGCCCCCCGAGCCCCCCGGGUCCAAGAUCCCCUCGCCCGGGGGAGGCUGCGUCACCUGGAGCUGCAUUGUCGCCCUUCUCGCCGGCUGCACUGGCAUUGGCAUCGGUUUCUAUGGCAACAGUGAGACCAGUGAUGGGGUGUCCCAGCUCAGCUCUGCGCUGCUGCACGCCAACCACACACUCAGCACCAUUGACCACCUGGUGUUGGAGACGGUGGAGAGGCUGGGCGAGGCGGUGAGGACAGAGCUGACCACCCUGGAGGAGGUGCUCGAGCCGCGCACGGAGCUGGUGGCUGCCGCCCGAGGGGCUCGACGGCAGGCGGAGGCUGCGGCCCAGCAGCUGCAGGGGCUGGCCUUCUGGCAGGGAGUGCCCCUGAGCCCCCUGCAGGUGGCUGAAAAUGUGUCCUUUGUGGAGGAGUACAGGUGGCUGGCCUACGUCCUCCUGCUGCUCCUGGAGCUGCUGGUCUGCCUCUUCACCCUCCUGGGCCUGGCGAAGCAGAGCAAGUGGCUGGUGAUCGUGAUGACAGUCAUGAGUCUCCUGGUUCUCGUCCUGAGCUGGGGCUCCAUGGGCCUGGAGGCAGCCACGGCCGUGGGCCUCAGUGACUUCUGCUCCAAUCCAGACCCUUAUGUUCUGAACCUGACCCAGGAGGAGACAGGGCUCAGCUCAGACAUCCUGAGCUAUUAUCUCCUCUGCAACCGGGCCGUCUCCAACCCCUUCCAACAGAGGCUGACUCUGUCCCAGCGAGCUCUGGCCAACAUCCACUCCCAGCUGCUGGGCCUGGAGCGAGAAGCUGUGCCUCAGUUCCCUUCAGCGCAGAAGCCUCUGCUGUCCUUGGAGGAGACUCUGAAUGUGACAGAAGGAAAUUUCCACCAGUUGGUGGCACUGCUACACUGCCGCAGCCUGCACAAGGACUAUGGUGCAGCCCUGCGGGGCCUGUGCGAAGACGCCCUGGAAGGCCUGCUCUUCCUGCUACUCUUCUCCCUGCUGUCUGCAGGAGCGCUGGCCACUGCCCUCUGCAGCCUGCCCCGAGCCUGGGCCCUCUUCCCACCCAGUGACGACUACGAUGACACAGACGAUGACGACCCUUUCAACCCUCAGCAGGAAUCCAAGCGCUUUGUGCAGUGGCAGUCGUCUAUCUGAGCCCCUCCUCCCGGCUGGACUGGAGCCUGGCUCCCCUCUUCGUUCCUUCCCUGGCUGCCGGAGGAGACCCCACUAACCCAGCCUGCCUGGGCUCUGACCACUAACACUCUUGGCCAUGGACAGCCUGCACAGGACCGCCUCCCUGCUCUUGGCCACUGUGCUCCCAUUUCUGUCCUUGGCCUUGGGAGUAGCUGAGGGGGCAGACUAGGGAGUAGGGCUGGCAGGGGAGGGGGCAGACAGCCUCGCCUCGCACCCUUCAUCCCUGGCUGCCGGUCCCAUCCUUGGAGGGACUAAGCUGGGGGUGGGGGACAUGAGUCCCCCUGCUGCCCCUGCCACAUCCCAGUGGGCUCUGACCCCCUGAUCUCAACUCGUGGCACUAACUUGGAAAAGGGUUGAUUUAAAAUAAAAGGGAAGACUAUUUUACAAGCAGCUGGGUCCUCCUUAUUUCUCCUCUCCCUUGAUUCGGCCUCCUGGCCAGGGCUGGGACAUCCUCCCUGCUGUCCUCUCUCCCCCGGCCUCCCAGCUGCCAGGAAUUUCUGCGCCUGUCCAGGCUCAGCAAGGGGUCCAAAGACAUUGUUCUUUAAAAAAAAAAAAAAAAAAAUCAAAAAACAAAA